AGCUUGAGAGACCAGCUCGGGUCUGAAGUGUUUCUCUAUCUACUGUGCUGAGAUCUCUCCUUCUCGAACCCUGCUAUGCCUUUGCAUACGCUGUUUUCUCCACCUGCCACGUUCUCACCCCUUCUUCUUCCACUGCAAACUCCUAUGCAGCCGUCAAGGCCCCAUUCUCCUCUGGAAAGCCUUCCCGAUCCCCUUGGCAACAACCACCACCAAUAUUUAUUCACUGAGCCCACUUUGUGCCAAGCAUUGUUCUAGACACGGAGAGGAGGAAGCUCCUGCCGGCUGAGCGGGCCUGGAGGAAGUGAGCAGCGGGGCUCCUGCCUCCCGGCCUGGUCCCCGAAGACCCCAGAAGAACCCGGAACUUGCUUCCAUUCGGAAUCCAGGGACCACCCUUUGCACUCAGUAGGCCUUUGUUUUCCUGCGUGGAAAGCGGUUGGGCUUGGGAGGCGAUGGAGCCGGAGUUCUUGUACGACCUGCUGCAGCUCCCCAAGGGGGUGGAGCCCCCAGCGGAGGAGGAGCUCUCAAAAGGAGGAAAGAAGAAAUACCUGCCACCCACUUCCCGGAAGGACCCCAAAUUUGAAGAACUGCAGAAGGUGUUGAUGGAGUGGAUCAAUGCCACUCUUCUCCCCGAGCACAUUGUGGUCCGCAGCCUGGAGGAGGACAUGUUCGACGGGCUCAUCCUACACCACCUAUUCCAGAGGCUGGCGGCGCUCAAGCUGGAAGCAGAGGACAUCGCCCUGACAGCCACAAGCCAGAAGCACAAGCUCACAGUGGUGCUGGAGGCCGUGAACCGGAGUCUGCAGCUGGAGGAGUGGCAGGCCAAGUGGAGCGUGGAGAGCAUCUUCAACAAGGACCUGUUGUCUACCCUGCACCUCCUUGUGGCCCUGGCCAAGCGCUUCCAGCCCGACCUCUCCCUCCCAACCAACGUCCAGGUGGAGGUCAUCACUAUCGAGAGCACCAAAAGUGGUCUGAAGUCAGAGAAGUUGGUGGAACAGCUCACUGAAUACAGCACAGACAAGGACGAGCCUCCAAAGGACGUCUUUGAUGAAUUAUUUAAGCUGGCUCCGGAGAAAGUGAACGCAGUGAAAGAGGCCAUCGUGAACUUUGUCAACCAGAAGCUGGACCGCCUGGGCCUGUCUGUGCAGAAUCUGGACACCCAGUUUGCAGAUGGGGUCAUCUUACUCUUGCUGAUUGGACAACUUGAAGGCUUCUUCCUGCACUUAAAGGAAUUCUACCUCACUCCCAACUCUCCUGCAGAAAUGCUGCACAACGUCACCCUGGCGCUGGAGCUGCUGAAGGACGAGGGCCUGCUCAGCUGCCCUGUCAGCCCUGAAGAUAUCGUGAACAAGGAUGCCAAGAGCACACUGAGGGUGCUCUAUGGUCUGUUCUGCAAGCACACGCAGAAGGCACACAGGGACAGGACGCCCCAUGGAGCCCCGAAUUGACCCUCACUGCCUCCAAAGCCCAGAGCCUGCCUGUCAGCCCAGCUGGAGGGCCCGAGGCUGCAGGGUGUCCUCCCACAGUCCCGCUGUUUCCUGUGCAUUCGUGACCCGCUUCCCUCCCACCCUGUCUCCUGUCUCCAUCGUUGGAUUAUCUUUGAACCCCCUUGUGUGGAUCAUUUUGAGCCGCCUGGCCUUGCUCAGUUUAUUUUAAUAAAAGUAUUUCUGGGAGGGAUUCUGGGAACUUGACAGGGUCCUGAGGAGGGCCCUUAAACCUGCAGCCUCCCUCCCAUGGGGUGAGUGUGUGUCACAUCAGUCUCUCAUCUCUGGGCCCAGGCUAGUGACCGCCCAGAGAGGUGGCAUCACUCAGGGCUGGGGACUCUCAGGGACAGGGCCCACAGCCCCAGACCCCACCUUUUCCAGCCCAGCUCCCCACACCCACCUGCUUCUCACUCGGGAGGAUGGGCCCCAGAGUCACCCUCCAGGGCAGGAGCCCGAAUGGCUCCAUAGCCAUGCCCCCACCCACCGGGAGAAGUGGAUUCAGUGACUGUCAAAGCAACCCGGGCUGUGUCCUGCAGCUGCCCUCGUGAGUUUUGCCCAAAAGUCACAAAGAAGCAAUCUUCGUGGUUGAUUAGUGGGUUCAGGUCAUCUCCAGUCUGUCCUCGGGAGCUGUGGGUUCCCACUCGCUCCAGUGAGACUUGGCAUUUUCUGCACAUAAAGAAGAGUCGUGUGGGAGAAUUGCACAUAGUCAGUCCAGGGCAUCCAGAGUGGGGCAGAGCUGAUGGCUGAUGGGAACCGGGGAGGAGGCUGGCGGGGAGGGGUGAGAUUGGUGGGGAGGGCUGGGGCUGGCCGGGAGGGGUGGGACUGAUGGGGAGGGGUGAGGCUGGCGGGGAGGGGUGAGGCUGGCGGGGAGGGGUGGGACUGGUGGGGAGGAGUGAGGCUAGUGGGCGGGUGAGGCUGGCGGGGAGGGGAGGGUUUGUGGGGACGGGUGAGGCUGGCGGGGAGGGGUGAGGCUGGUGGGGAGGGCUGGGGCCUGGUGGGGAGGAGUGGGACUUGUGGGGAGGAGUGGGACUUGUGGGGAGGGGUGAGGCUGGGGAGAAGGGCAACCACAGCCCCAGGCUGCUGCUCCUCCCUGGACCCUGAAGAGGCCUCUGGGUCUGGGGUUUUCACAGUUUGACAGCUGAGGCCUUGGGGAGGGGCUUUAGAUGGGGGUUAGGGGCUAGGUCAUCAUUGACACCCACUGGGGGCGCCUAGGCAGAUGUCCUUCGGGGGAGCAAGAUGGGAGCCAGGGACGCAGUGCCAGGUCAGCCCUGGGAGCUGGUGUCUGGGUGUGAGAAGGCCUUGAGGGGUCUUCCCUUCACCUAGCCUCCCAUCUGCCUGCCCUUCUCAGCUCCCAAUUCACAGGGCAAACCCAAGCCCAUAAGCGUGUUCCACGUGAGCACUCAGAUGCACCCCUCUUCAUGGAUACCCACCCUACUUCCCGGCUGCCUCUGGGAAACGUGCAUCCUCCCACACCAGGUACCUGGAGCCCAGCUCCUUCCACCUGCUCAGGUGCCCCCUCCAUUGCGAUGCCCCCUCCAGCACCUCAAAUCCUCUCCUGGAGCUUCUGGGGACACAGGCUCAGCCUCUCUCAGCUGGCUUCAUCCCAAAAGCCUGAAAUCCAGCCCCACUUCCUGGGGCCUUUGAGUCCUCACUUGCUUGGGCCCCAUCCGCUGCAGGCUGGCUCUGCCUGGCUGUUCCACGUCCUCACUCUUGUUCUAUUUGACAGCAAUUAAAAAAAAAGUGACUUAUUUAAUUACUGUAGCUUUAUUGAAAAAUAACUUCCCAGUUUGAAGUGUACAAUUUGAUGAGUUUUGACAAAUGCAUGCAGUCAUAUAACCACCACCAUCGUUAUCCAGACAUGGGACAUUCCCAUCACCAUGCAAGUUUCUGCAUCUGUCUGCAGCCAGUUCCCUUCUCCCAGCCCCUGGCCCUGGGGACCACUGAUCUGUUUUCUGUCACCAUCAUUUAGACUUGUCUAGAAUUUCUUAUAAACUGUAUCCUAUGGUA